AGAAAACCUCCCCUCCUGGUCUACCCACGCCUGGACUCAGAAGAGACUCUCCACCUCAAAGGAUAGUGCUCCAGCUACUGCUUCUCUUAUGGUAACCCCCGACACCUGCACAUUCUGAUUGGGACCUCAGUGGUCAUCAUCCUCUUCAUCCUCCUCUUCUUUCUCCUUCAUCGCUGGUGCUCCAACAAAAAAAAUGCUGCGGUAAUGGACCAAGAGUCUGCAGGAAACAGAACAGCGAAUAGCGAGGACUCUGAUGAACAAGACCCUCAGGAGGUGACAUACACACAGUUGAAUCACUGCGUUUUCACACAGAGAAAAAUCACUCGCCCUUCUCAGAGGCCCAAGACACCCCCAACAGAUAUCAUCGUGUACACGGAACUUCCAAAUGCUGAGUCCAGAUCCAAAGUUGUCUCCUGCCCAUGAGCACCACAGUCAGGCCUUGAGGGCGUCUUCUAGGGAGACAACAGCCCUGUCUCAAAACCGGGUUGCCAGCUCCCAUGUACCAGCAGCUGGAAUCUGAAGGCAUGAGUCUGCAUCUUAGGGCAUCGAUCUUCCUCACACCACAAAUCUGAAUGUGCCUCUCACUUGCUUACAAAUGUCUAAGGUCCCCACUGCCUGCUGGAGAAAAAACACACUCCUUUGCUUAGCCCACAGUUCUCCAUUUCACUUGACCCCUGCCCACCUCUCCAACCUAACUGGCUUACUUCCUAGUCUACUUGAGGCUGCAAUCACACUGAGGAACUCACAAUUCCAAACAUACAAGAGGCUCCCUCUUAACGCAGCACUUAGACACGUGUUGUUCCACCUUCCCUCAUGCUGUUCCACCUCCCCUCAGACUAGCUUUCAGUCUUCUGUCAGCAGUAAAACUUAUAUAUUUUUUAAAAUAACUUCAAUGUAGUUUUCCAUCCUUCAAAUAAACAUGUCUGCCCCCA